GAGUUACGUCAGCGAGAGCUGCAAAGUUCCUUGCUAUUCUUUUCUGGUGUCGGGGAGCUGAAUAUUAAAAGGGUGAUUGUGGAGUUACCGGUUAUCUGCAUUUUUUUUUCUUUUCUUAUUUUGACUCUUUUUAAAAAAUGCAGGUAAAGUGACAGCGGUUCAGGAGCUUAAAGACAUCAGUGGUGGAGGGGUGAGUCAGCGGGUGCAAAAGGACAAGGAUUUGGUGCCUCGGAGACACGGUCCCCUCUCCGCCUCCAGAGAAGAGCAGGCAGGCAGCUCCCGGGACCGAAGCCGGGUCCACAUCCCCCGCGCGCGAGCUGGUGGCUCAGCAGCGGCGCUUCAGGUGGACGCGGUCAAACGAUGCCCCGCAGCCUCCUGGGUCUCAGCACAUAUUCCACACCUACGUCCCCUGACCUGUGCUCCUAGAAGCUGGAGAGAGCAGGAGCCUUCGGUGGGGCAGCUCAAAAUGUAGGUAACUGCGGGCCAGGAGCAGCGCCCAACCUGUAGCGCUGCGCUACCCAACCAUCGGUCCCUGCCUUUGAGCGUCGACGGCUGAUCUUUUGGUUUGAGGGAGAGACUGGCGCUGGAGUUUUGAAUUCCGAAUCAUGUGCAGAAUGCUGAAUCUUCCCCCAGCCAGGACGAAUAAGACAGCGCGGAAAAGCAGAUUCUCGUAAUUCUGGAAUUGCAUGUUGCAAGGAGUCUCCUGGAUCUUCGCACCCAGCUUCGGGUAGGGAGGGAGUCCGGGUCCCGGGCUAGGCCAGCCCGGCAGGUGGAGAGGGUCCCCGGCAGCCCCGCGCGCCCCUGGCCAUGUCUUUAAUGCCCUGCCCCUUCAUGUGGCCUUCUGAGGGUUCCCAGGGCUGGCCAGGGUUGUUUCCCACCCGCGCGCGCGCUCUCACCCCCAGCCAAACCCACCUGGCAGGGCUCCCUCCAGCCGAGACCUUUUGAUUCCCGGCUCCCGCGCUCCCGCCUCCGCGCCAGCCCGGGAGGUGGCCCUGGACAGCCGGACCUCGCCCGGCCCCGGCUGGGACCAUGGUGUUUCUCUCGGGAAAUGCUUCCGACAGCUCCAACUGCACCCAACCGCCGGCACCGGUGAACAUUUCCAAGGCCAUUCUGCUCGGGGUGAUCUUGGGGGGCCUCAUUCUUUUCGGGGUGCUGGGUAACAUCCUAGUGAUCCUCUCCGUAGCCUGUCACCGACACCUGCACUCAGUCACGCACUACUACAUCGUCAACCUGGCGGUGGCCGACCUCCUGCUCACCUCCACGGUGCUGCCCUUCUCCGCCAUCUUCGAGGUCCUAGGCUACUGGGCCUUCGGCAGGGUCUUCUGCAACAUCUGGGCGGCAGUGGAUGUGCUGUGCUGCACCGCGUCCAUCAUGGGCCUCUGCAUCAUCUCCAUCGACCGCUACAUCGGCGUGAGCUACCCGCUGCGCUACCCAACCAUCGUCACCCAGAGGAGGGGUCUCAUGGCUCUGCUCUGCGUCUGGGCACUCUCCCUGGUCAUAUCCAUUGGACCCCUGUUCGGCUGGAGGCAGCCGGCCCCCGAGGACGAGACCAUCUGCCAGAUCAACGAGGAGCCGGGCUACGUGCUCUUCUCAGCGCUGGGCUCCUUCUACCUGCCUCUGGCCAUCAUCCUGGUCAUGUACUGCCGCGUCUACGUGGUGGCCAAGAGGGAGAGCCGGGGCCUCAAGUCUGGCCUCAAGACCGACAAGUCGGACUCGGAGCAAGUGACGCUCCGCAUCCAUCGGAAAAACGCCCCGGCAGGAGGCAGCGGGAUGGCCAGCGCCAAGACCAAGACGCACUUCUCAGUGAGGCUCCUCAAGUUCUCCCGGGAGAAGAAAGCGGCCAAAACGCUGGGCAUCGUGGUCGGCUGCUUCGUCCUCUGCUGGCUGCCUUUUUUCUUAGUCAUGCCCAUUGGGAAAAAAAUGAAGAAACUUAAGGUUCCAUGGCCUGAGGAAGGCCACAGAAGGAAACUCACUUUGAGCUGAGCUUUGAGGGGCAGGAAGUACUAGCUCAGCUGGAAUGCACCCUCUGUUCAUGAUCUCCAUGACGAAAAUGAACUCAUUGUGUAAGUGAGCUGGCCAUCUUCUCAGGAAGAAGAGGUAAGCACUCUCUGGACAGAAUGUGUUUAUGUGUUUUUGGCAUGGCCAGUGCCCAGCUCAGCACUUGGGACAUUGUAGGAAUUCAAGGAAUGGGGCUCAUGUCCUCAUGCAAACACCAGUGCGCAGAACUUGGAAGUCGAUUUUCUGUUUUAAGCAGGUAUCAAACAGGCAAUCAACACUGUGCCUAGUAUCGAACCAGAAUGCCCGCAGGAUACAAGGGAGACUGUUCCUUAAGGAUUGUUAAAUCAGGAGGGAGAGUAUAAAUUAGCGUGCAUGUGCAAUUCAUAUAUCAUUACAAGCUAAAUUUUGAUUUUUCCUAAAGAAUGACAGUUGCUCUGUGAAGGCUGACAUAGUUGAAAAAGACUUUUUGGAGGAAGUGAAGCUUGAUCUGGGAUUAGUGAAUAAGUGGGAUAUAAGUAUCAAAAUUAGGAAAUUUUGACAAGGAUAGCUGACAACUAGAAGUUGGGGUAAUAUGGCCUUUAGGGGAUGAGAAGCCCCACGAUGACCAGUGAAAAGUGUUCCUGGUCCCCUUAUAGGAAACGAAGUAGGGCGGAAUUAGAAAACAAAGAAACUCCAUCUUCCUCCCUACCCACCCUCCCCAUUUUUUGUCAAACAACCAAACUCUCCCACUUGAGUGUUUCAUGGAAGAAUGGUUAAAGGCAGGAAGAAGAGAGAAGAAAAGAAAAGGAGCUGAGCUACAAUCAGAAAGAAGAAAACAAGCUAGAGAGUGAAGAUAUCUCUAUGACCCCCAUUCCCUAAAGAAGGAACUGUCUCCUCUCUCCCAACACAGAUGUGGGGACCGAGGCCCUGGAAGGCCUAGCAAGCUCAGGGUGGGACAUGUGGGGGCUGGGGGUCUCUCUGGAGCAUGCAGGCAUUGUUUUAUGCCAUGCUUGAAUUCUGAACAACCAAACGCUGUCAGAAGGAAGCUGGCAUGUUGCUCCACUGGUAACUCAAUUCCACACUGCAGAUCUGCCGGCUAGUUCAAGAAGAACUACGAUGCCAUCAAAAUCCAAUGUUCAAUCAGAGAAGGAAGCUGCCUUCUCUUUCUGCAGAUGAUUAAGAGGCAGACAUACUCAUGCAUUGGAGAGUCUUGCUGUCUUUUCUUCCAGGAAUAAAGAUGGGCUCAUUUAACAUGAUUUCUACCUGUUCUCCUGCAAUUAGUGUUUAAGUGACUGUCUCUGGGUAUUAGUCACUCUGAGGAAAUGAAAUGAUGCUAUGGUAAUUGGCCAUGUGUGUGUUUUUUCUUUUCUUUUCACUUCCCUAGGGAUUUCACUUGGCUCAGAAAGCAUUUUUUAACAUAGGCCCUGUCUGCACUCUUUAUUUAGCUAAUUAGAGAGCUUAAGGGAGCAUGCUGGCAUUGAGCAAAAAGGGAGGAAGGGGGAGGGGCAGCGUGUUCUACUGGGAAGAGCACUCGAUUGAACAGGAAUAUCUGGGUUCUAGCCCAAACUCAUCAAUUUUCUCUUCUAUUAAGCUCUUAAAUUUUGGUCAGCUGUGUGACAGGCAUUACCUUGUUCGAUCCUCACAAUAACCUUACAAUGUUGGUAUCAUGGCCUCCUUUCAGAGAUGCAAAAAACGAAGUUUGAAGGAGGCUGCCUUGACCGUGGCUUCCCGGCGGGCAUGCAACAGGGCUGACACGGAGACUCUAGUUGGCCUUAAUUCCUAUGCUUUGCCAUCCUUUAUUAGUUUUUGCUUACUAGAUAGACCCCUGUUACCCAGGAUGAGUCACUUCACUUCUCUGUCCUUGCUUGCUUAAACUGUUCGUGAUUCUGUAAAAAUGCUGGCUCUUCUGAAGUUCUAAGUGCCUUUCUUUCUGAACAGAUGGAAAAAUAUUAUAUAUCCUUUCUAUUACCUUUCUAAUACCUUUCUCUUUCCUUGCCCCCUACCUAUUUUGUUCUGCUUUUCUUCUCUCUCCUACUACAUCCAGACAGUGGCCAGUACAGCAGGUGUGGGGGCUGAGCAAGAAGAGGCAGGGGGAGGAGAAAGAAGCAGCUCUAUUCAUUGGGCACUCCAUUUUCCAGCCCAGGGCAAUACUUUCUUCUAAAUGAGCCCAGAGUAACAUAGCGUGGAACAAAGACCCAAAGAAAGGCUUGGAGUAUGAAGAUUUCAUUUCCAAUUCUGCCGCUGUCUUACUAUAUUGUGGGGUUUUGACCAAGCCAUAGUCUUAUGGUACCUCGGGUUCUUCACCUUGACAACUAUAAUUAUAACACACAUCAGAGAGUGGUUGUGCCCUUGAAGUUGCAAGAAUAUGAGGUGUCAAGUAUGAGUGAUGAAAUGAUGGUCCUGGUAGGGGUCCUAGGCCAACUAGUCCUGAUCCUCUGUCUUAUAGGAAAAAGGAAGGUGGGCUUCCUGGUGCCACUUAGAUAGGUGGUGACACAAAUAUGUUGAUAGCCCAAGCAGCCUGAUCCUUAGCCCAGCGCUCCCCGAACCAGUGCAUUUGUCCCAACUUCCAAGAUGGAGGAAAGGUUUUGUUCUUCAUAGAAUUCAGUUUUUAUGAGAGAACAAUAAUUACCUGUCAAUGAAACACCUCUGCUUUCUCUAGCUAACAUUUUAGAAGGUAUCAGAGAUACGGCUCACCAGGGACAAAGAUAUUACACUGGUGUGCAUUCCCAUUCAUGACCUAUCUUGAUGAUGAAUUCUGUGAGGCUGUGCUCCAUGAGGAAGCAGAUGGAAGUCACCGCCCAUGCCCAGCCCCCAGCACGUGACAGUGUGGAAGGCAGACACUAUACCAUGUGGCCAAAGAAGCAUGUGUCACAGACAAGAGCACACUUUGCAGAAAGGCUAGCCACAUAUUUUGCUUCAUGACACUGCCCUCCCCCAUUUUUUGUUCAUUUCUUGCUGGUGUUUGUUCUUCUGUUAAUGCCUAUAACAAAAAAUUACAGUUCACAGUUGGAAAGGAGAGAAAAACUUUCUUGGCCUGUGAUAUGGUUUGGAUCUGUGUCCCCACCCAAAUCUCAUGUCAAAUUGUAAUCCCUAAUGCUGGAAGUGGGGCCUGGUGGGAGGUGACUGACUCAAAGGGUGGUUUCUCAUAGUUUGACACCAUCUUCCCUUGGUGCUGUCAUCAUGAUAGUGAGCUGUCAUGAGAUUUGUUUAUUAAAAGUGUGUGGCACCUCCUCCCACCACUUUCUUGCUUCUGCUCCAGCUAUGUGCCUCCUUCCCCUUCACCUUCCACCACGAUUGUAAGUUUCCUGAGAUCUCCCCAGAAGCGGAAGUCACCAUGCUUCCUGCAUGGCCUGCAGAACCAUGAGCCAGUUAAACUUCUUUUCUUUAUAAAUUACCCAGUCUCAGGCAUUCCUUUGUAGCAAUGUGAGAACAGACUAAUACAGCCUGUAUCUAAACCAUCCUUGAGUAAGUUAUUGUCUAUAAAUAGCACCUUAGGUUGUAUACUACAAUGUCUUUCAUGCAGUUUUCUUUUGCAUUUUUCUUCAUUCUGCAUCAACCUUGUGAGGAUUAUUGUAAUCUUCAUUUUGUAAGAAUGUAAAUCUGUGCUGUCUGAUAUAGUAGCCACUAGCCAUGUAUGGCUAUUUUAAUUUAAGUGACUUAAAAUUGAGUAAAUGAAAAGCUUCACUUCCUCAAUGAUCCUGGCCACAUUUCAAGUUCUGAGUAGUUGCAUGCUAAGAACUUGUUUGUAUAAUCCCUUUUAGCCCUCAGACAAUUUAACAAAACAUUUUAUGAAGUAGGCAUAGCUUUAUAGACAAAGAAGCUGAGUCUUGGAGAGAUUUGCUCUCAUAUCAAGACACAUACAACUCAAAAGUGGUGGAUAUCUCUUGGUUUGGCUCCACAGUUUUCUCUCUCAACCACGAUACCAUACUUUGGAAAGACUUUCACAAAUUCUUAAAAAUAUGAACAUGCAAUUACCAUUCAACCCAGUAGUUGUUCUUCUGGCCACAUAUUCUAGAGAGAUGAAAAUUUAUGGUCACACAAAAAACUUGUACAGGAGUUUUUACAGCAGCUUUAUUUGUAAUAGCCCCAAACUGGAAACAAUCCAGAUAUUCAUCAGUGAAUGAAGGGUUAAGCAAAUGGUAAUACACCCCUACUUAGCAAUAAAAAAUAGCAAGCUAUUGAUAUGUGCAACAUUCUCUAGAUGAAGUACCAGAGAAUAAUGCUAAGUGGAAAAAGCCAAUCCCAAAAUGAUUGCAUACUGUAUGACUCUAUUUACAUAACAUUCUUGAAAUGACAAAAUUAUAGAAAUAGAGAACAGAUUAGUGAUUUCCAGGAGUGAAGAUCGGGGUGGGGCAGAAGGGAAGUGGGUAUGGCUAUAAAAGGACUAUUUGAGAGCUCCUUGCCAGGAUGGAACUAUUCUGUAUCUUGACUGUAUCGUUGUCAAUAUCCUGGUUGUGAUAUUGUACCGUAGUUUUGCAAGAUGUUGCCAUUGGAUGAAACCUGGUAAUGUGGUUUGAAUGUUUGCCCCCUCCAAAUCUCGUGUUGAAAUGUGAUUCCCAAUGUUGGAGGUGGGGCCUGGUGGGAGGUGAUUGGAUCAGGGAGUUGGCUUCCUCAUGAAUGGCUUAACACCAUCUCCGUGGUGAAAAGUGAGUUCUCAGUUCACUCGAGGUCUGCUUGUUUAAAAGUCUGAGGCCUCCCCACUCCCUUGCUCUGUCUUGCUCCCACUCUCACCAUGUGAUAUUUCCUGCUCUCCCUUAGCCUUCCACCAUGACUGUAUGCUUCCUGAGGCC